UCUUUUUUAAACUAUUCUUUUCUGGCACCUUAAUGAGUGAGCAGCAAAUGAACCCCAUGAACUUAUUCAUAUUGAACCAAUAUUUAUUAAAUAUCUACUAUGUGACAAGCACCAAUAUGUAUCACAAAGGUAUGUCACAAUGAGAAUGGAGGUCAGAAGAAAAGUGUGGAUAAAGGGUUAAGGGAUUAUGGAAGAGGUUGCAAGUAACUCGAGAAAUGGAUCAGAUUUGGGGUUUAAAUACACAUAGAAAUACACAAGGGGGAGAAGUGAAGAGUCAAAGGGCAUUUCAAGUUCACCAUGUGCAAAGGAAGAUGGAGAAGUGAACACUAAUGCUUCAGGAAUGACGAAAAGAUGGUGCAUAAAAUGUUCCAUAACCUGCCUUCUGUGGAUCUCAUACUAAAUCUUGCUACUUCUUGCAUCAUACAUUACAUUUAUCUUCUGUGCCAUUGACUGUGCAAUCUACUCUAUUUAGAUGACUGCCUUUCACUCUUCAUUUCUCCUGGUUAAUGUCUUUAUACAAGUCUUCUCCACUCAACUAUGGAUUCCUUGGAGACAGGCAGACAUCUUAUUCAUCUUUGUAUCCCAGCACAUAACACAAUUCUUGGCACAAUGCAGGCAUUCUAUAAAUGCCUAUUGAAUCCACUGAUACAUCUAUCCACCAACAAAGUUAGGGAGCACUUUCUUUUGUCAUUGGUUGUUGCAUAAGUUCACAACAGUUAAAAAAAAAAAAAAGACAUGGUAAUCUAAGGAAGAAAGUAGCAGAUGAAUCUGAGAAAGUAGGUUGGGAACAGACAAUGAAAGGUCAGCCAGGCCACCUUAAAGAGGUUAGAAUUAACUUUGUGUGUAAUUUUCACCAAAGGUUUAUAUAGAGGGAAGAGGUACCAUUUUUAUAUAGAAACAUAUACAUAUAUAUAGUAAAACUUUAGAGAGGGCAGAGUCUUGUUGAAGUAGAAGAUUAAGUUAGGAUAUAUUUGUUGACUGUAGAGGACUGCAGAGUGGUGUAAGAGGUAGUGGAGAUGUUAACUGCAGAAGCAAAUCUUGUAAAACAAAAAAUCUGAGAGUGAAGACUCUCUUUGAAUCUAGUAAGAAUUGAGUUUGGUAAUAAAAAGGAACCAGUUGGAGGAGAAUCUGGCAGAUGUGUGUGGAUUUGAAAUAAAGAGUAACAAUGGACCACCAUGCCAAGGAGAACUAUGAAAUGAGAAUAAUAUUUGAGGAAGAGAAGUCAAUAAUUAUCCCCAUAAAAGAAGGGGUAUGACAAAGCAGAUGAGAGGUGAGCUAGGUAGCUCUGGCUAUUAACCAGCAUGCAAGUGAUAAAAGCCAAGGAUAGCUGGAAAAACAGAAAGAAACGAAUAUAAAACAAGUAAGAAUAGAACUUACUUCAUGAGUAGUACAUGAAAAUUUUUUUUUUGAAAAAGCUCUGUCACCAGGCUGGAGUGCAGUGGCGCGAUCUAGGCUCACAACAACUUGUGUCCGCCUCCUGGGUUCAAGCGAUUCUCGUGCCUCAGCCUUCUGAGUAGCUGGGAUUACAGGCAUGCAUCACCACACCCAGCUAAUUUUUGUAUUUUAGUAGACGGGGUUUCGCCAUGUUGGAACCAGGAUAUUCUCCAUCUCCUGACCUCCUGAUCUGCCCACCUUGGCCUCCCAAAGUGCUGGGAUUACAGGCAUGAGCCACCGUGCCUGGCUGAAAAUACUUUUUUAAGACCUAGUACCAGACUUCUUUAGAGAAGUAAUUACUAGUUUUUAGGAAAAGUGACUUUGAAUAGAGAAUGUGAGCUCUGUAAGGAAGGCUCAGGAGGAGCAAAACAAAGAUCACUGAUGUUCUUCACGAAAAGUAAAUGAGAAGACCUCCUCCAACAUGGUCGACUGAGCUUUCCUUUAUAAACUCAUAGAAAUAAUGGAUAAAAUAUAAUUAUUGUUCUAUAAACCAUAUACAACCGUAAAAACAAAAAACAGCAAAAAGGAAAUUCUCAGUGCCUGAAAUAAAUUUUAAAAAUUGAAGAGCAGAAAGCAGAACAGAUACUGCGGUAGCCCUCCAAAAUUUUAUACUUGGCUAUAUGCCUCAGGAGCCAGUAGUUGAGUUUUAAUGUCCAAGCACAAGGCUGAGCUUUGAUGAGGCAGGUGAGCUGGAACUAAGCCCUUAUGUAAAACCUGGAGCCUUAGGAAUAGCCAGCUACCGGAACUGGAAAAAGGCAAUCUACUAGUUUGGGGAAGCGAUAAAGAAGUUUGUUCUUUGGGGCUUUGGAUAGGGUGGGAAAAAAAAAACAUAAGGUACCUAUGAGAAAUCAAAACUGCAGCCCUGCAACAGAUCUAAAUAUACAAUAUUUGCAUAAUUCAGGAGCCACAAACUGAGAAAUUAUCAUUUGAAAAUGCUUCAGAUCUUUAAGAGCUACGGUAUGCUGGCAGAAGCAAAUGCAUAAUUGUCUAAAGGGACUCUUUUGCAACUAAGGGUGUAAGAGAGUCCCAUAAACAAAACCAUCCCACUGAAGAAGAGCACCACAUGAGGAAAUAAAUCACUGAGUAAGAGUCAGUGGAGGUCGUAAACAAGAGUUAGGAACUGAAAAGCUAAAAAUAACAGAACUAACAGAAAAGAAGAUAAAAUAAAGACAUAUAACUUGAUUAAAAGGACAAAAUAAUAGAAAUCAUAAUGAAAGAAGAGGCAGAAUUCACAAAGAACCAAACAGAACAUGUAUUUUAGAAAACAAUAUUGUCACUGACAUUAAAAUGAAUGGGUCUAACCAGUCCCACUGGGUGAAUGAAUAUAAUAACCUCCUUUUCUAUUCCUCAUUUUAAAUUAUACUUAGCUGUGUUUCUUUGCAAGUUUGUCAAACAGGUUAUAUUCGGUGAACCCACAGUUCAAAUAAUAUGGCGUUAGAAAUAAAAUACAGUCAUGCGUUGCCUAACGACGAGAUACGUUCUGAGAAACGCCUCAUUAGGCAAUUUCAUUGUUGUGCAAACAUCAUGAAGUAUACUUAACACAAACCUACAUAUUAUAGCCUUAUGAUUCUAGACUACAAACUUUUAUAGCAUAUUACUGUACUGAAUAAUGUAGGUAACUAUAACACAAUGUUGUGUUUGUGUUUCUAAACAGAAAGGGUAGUAUGUUGCACUACGAUGUUACAACAUCACUAAGCAACAGGAAUUAUCCAUUAUAAUCUUAAGGGACCACAGUCACAUAAUGUAAUCAGACAUUGAAAUAUUAUGUGGUGCACGAGUGUAUUCAAAAAGUGCUGCCAGGCCACUGCCCUCCAGCCUGAGACAGAGUGAGACUCCUUCUCUGAAAAAAUAAAAGUGCUGCUAGUCAAUCCAAUGUAAAAAUAUAAACUUCCUGUCAUUAUCAAUUCAUUUCCUUGAACCUAAAAAUAAUCUCUCAACAAAAUGAGUCUUCCUUACUUCUGCGGUAAAGUCCUUUCUUUUUUUCUUGUCCUUUGUUCCAAGGAGAAAGGAUUCACUCGGGUCCCUGUGAGAAGAGCUUCUUUAGCACUCUAAAAUUAGAAAAGUAUACCCAGGAGAGAGCAGGUUCCUUCCAGUUCCCUAGGAGAGUAGAGCACCAAAUAUUUCUCCUAGGUCUUGCUUUGUGGCUGUAUGUGUGUCCUUGCUGGUACUGAUGAUGCCUUCCAUAUAAGGACUCAGACUCCACUAGCUGCCAGAUUUCUGCUUGAAACACUGCCCGCUAGCGUUGAAGCUUUCAAACGAUUUUAAUCCAUGGUGAUGAAGCAAGAACAGUGUUUUCUGUACACUGCAUCUACCCUAUACUCUCUGUUUCUACCCCUCACAUCUCCAAAUUAGGGGGCUUCACUGGCUUUGUGCCUUGGUUUUUUCCACUCACCUGUGUGAUCUCAGGAGGCAGAGUUUCAAGUUAGUCAUCAGUGAUUUCCUCAAGUCCAUUUGUCUUAUAUUUAGCAGCAAUUCCUUAGUGCUUCUGGCACGCAAUAAGACUAAAACUGAGAGAUCUCCACCUUUAUAAGCAUUUUUCAUUUUAAUCAAUGGUCUUAAUGGGAGUAGUUAGAUCUGCACAUUCUUCUAACCACCCAGGAGUCCUUAUCCAACAACAGUGCACUUGUGUAUGUUUUCAUCCAUGUGACGUAAGUGUAUCAGCUAGUUGUUAAAGUGCAAAGACUAACAGUCUGUCUUAACACAUAUUUCCAUACCAAAAAAUCACUUUAUUUCACAACGUGACAAAGUCCACAUUAGGAUUUGUUGGCAAAUUAAAAUUCUUUACUCACAAAAUGAUAAAAGGAAGGAGACACAGCUCAAAGUUAAUGUGUAAGAGUUAACAGAAUCAAUACAAGUGAAUAGCUGUGGAGCCCAGGGGAUGCAGGAAUCAAGGCAGACAAAGAUAUCUGUUGAAUUAAAUUAAUGUUAGGUCACUACCCAUGGUUGACAUCACAGAAGUGGAUAAGCAUACCAGAGUAAACAAAGGAAUCCUUUCUUAAACAAAAAACCCAUACAACUUAUUUUACUCCCUUAUCGAGAAAUAUUUUCAAAAUAUAAGCCCAUUCCUGGUAGGUUAAGACCAAUUCAGAUGACUGCAUUGCCAUUCCAGGGCCAAGAAAGCAACUUUAAAAACAUGACCUACGCUAUGGUCUAAAUGUGUCCCUCAAAAUGCACAUUUUGAAAUCCUAACUCCCGAACUGACGGUUUUAGCAAGUGGCAUCUUGGGAAGUGAGGAAUGGGAUUAAGGUCCUUAUAAAAUAGGCCCAAGCGAGGGCCUCUGCCUCUCCACCAUGCGAGGACAGAGCCAGAAGGUGCUAUCCACUAAAGAGAAAGCACCCCUCCCUAGACACACCUUAUUCUGUGACAUUCCAGCCUUCAGAAAUGUGAAGAAUAAACUUCUGUGGUUCAUAAACUACCCAGUCUAGGAUAUUUUGUUAUGGAAGCCCAAAAGGAUCAAGCCAUUCCAAAAUAGCAUUGUUGCCCACACCAUCUUUUUGAACCUCACUUAGGGUAACACCAUACCCAUUCGGAGUUAAGCCCUUCCUAACUCUUAAGUAUCAACGUGCUUGGAAACGUGAGCAAUCCUGACACGUUUUUUCUUCCUAAAGAACAAUACAUACUAAUAAUAGGAUCGGCUAAUAAUACUAGAUUCUAUGCAUGAAGCCUAGUAUUUAAAAGCAUGCAAUCUGGAGCUAGACCGCCUGGGAACAAAUCCCAGCUUACUAGACAAGCUGUUUAACCUUUUACUUGGUCUCAUUUAACUCAUUUGUAAAACGAGGGCAAUUUCUGAUUUCAUAGGGUUGCUACGUGGAUUUUAAAAAGCCCCUUGCAAUAUAGCCUAAUAUUCAGAACUCAAUAACAUGAACUGUCUUAAAAGGUUUCCAGAAAAAAUCCCCAACAGGUUAGGUCGGCUUAUCAUUACAACGCUUUCCGGUAUAAGGGAGAUGAAUAGCUAUUUAGCACCACACAAUUUCUCCUCUGGGCUCGGAACAGCUCUCGGUAGACUACGAUCCCUUUCCGACGUGGAAACUUCAGAUAAAAACGCUCCCCGAGGUCCGAGGCCAGUACGGGGCGGAGCCAGGACGCGGGCCAGAGUCCCCCGAAGGACGGUGCCUCUCUGGCCCCAAGAAGUACAGCUUUUAUUUUGCAGCAAUCUGAGCCAACCCGAGAAGAUUCUGAAGCUUCCAAAACAGAACCGACGAGAACACUCAUAGAAUGCCUCUCCACUUCCUAACUGUCGCUUUGAGGAGAGAAAAAACUGGUUUGUGGCCUGUUUGAUUCCUGUCAGAGGUUUGCUGACCCAAGACAGUAUCGAAAAUGCAUAUUAAGUCAAUUAUUCUAGAGGGAUUCAAGUCCUAUGCUCAGAGGACCGAAGUCAAUGGUUUUGACCCCCUCUUCAAUGCUAUCACUGGCUUAAAUGGUAGUGGGAAAUCCAACAUAUUGGACUCCAUCUGCUUUUUGCUGGGCAUCUCCAACCUGUCUCAGGUUCGGGCUUCUAAUUUACAAGAUUUAGUUUACAAAAAUGGGCAGGCUGGUAUUACCAAAGCCUCUGUGUCAAUCACUUUUGAUAAUUCUGACAAAAAGCAAAGUCCUUUAGGAUUUGAGGUUCAUGAUGAAAUCACAGUAACAAGGCAGGUGGUUAUUGGUGGUAGAAAUAAAUAUUUAAUCAAUGGAGUCAAUGCCAACAACACCAGAGUACAGGAUCUCUUCUGUUCUGUUGGCCUUAAUGUUAACAACCCUCACUUUCUCAUCAUGCAGGGCCGAAUUACAAAAGUAUUGAAUAUGAAACCUCCAGAGAUUUUAUCCAUGAUAGAAGAAGCAGCUGGAACCAGGAUGUAUGAAUACAAAAAAAUAGCUGCACAGAAAACUAUAGAAAAAAAGGAGGCUAAGCUGAAAGAAAUUAAGACGAUACUUGAAGAAGAGAUUACUCCAACCAUUCAAAAAUUAAAAGAGGAAAGAUCGUCCUACUUGGAGUACCAAAAAGUAAUGAGAGAAAUAGAACAUUUGAGUCGUUUAUAUAUUGCUUAUCAGUUUUUGCUGGCUGAAGAUACCAAAGUACGCUCAGCUGAGGAAUUAAAAGAAAUGCAAGAUAAAGUUAUAAAGCUUCAGGAAGAAUUGUCUGAGAAUGAUAAAAAAAUAAAAGCACUUAAUCAUGAAAUAGAAGAAUUGGAAAAAAGAAAAGAUAAGGAAACUGGAGGUAUACUUCGAUCUUUAGAAGAUGCUCUUGCAGAGGCUCAGCGAGUUAAUACUAAAUCUCAAAGCGCAUUUGAUCUCAAGAAGAAAAAUCUGGCAUGUGAGGAAAGCAAACGCAAAGAGCUGGAAAAAAAUAUGGUUGAGGACUCAAAAACUUUAGCAGCAAAGGAAAAAGAGGUUAAAAAGAUAACAGAUGGACUGCAUGCCCUUCAAGAAGCAAGUAAUAAAGAUGCUGAAGCUCUGGCAGCUGCACAGCAGCACUUCAAUGCUGUUUCCGCUGGCCUGUCCAGUAAUGAAGAUGGAGCAGAAGCAACUCUUGCUGGUCAAAUGAUGGCCUGUAAAAAUGAUAUAAGUAAAGCUCAGACAGAAGCCAAACAGGCUCAGAUGAAGUUGAAGCAUGCUCAACAGGAAUUAAAGAAUAAACAAGCUGAAGUUAAGAAGAUGGAUAGUGGCUACAGGAAGGAUCAAGAAGCUCUAGAAGCUGUAAAAAGACUUAAAGAAAAACUUGAAGCUGAAAUGAAAAAGCUAAAUUAUGAAGAAAAUAAAGAGGAAAGCCUUUUGGAAAAGCGCAGGCAGCUGUCUCGUGAUAUUGGUAGAUUGAAAGAAACAUAUGAAGCUCUAUUAGCCAGAUUUCCCAAUCUUCGAUUUGCAUACAAGGAUCCAGAGAAGAACUGGAAUAGAAAUUGUGUGAAAGGACUUGUGGCUUCUCUGAUUAGUGUGAAAGACACUUCUGCAACCACAGCUUUAGAAUUAGUGGCUGGAGAACGACUCUACAAUGUUGUAGUAGACACAGAAGUUACUGGUAAAAAGCUACUAGAAAGGGGGGAACUGAAACGUCGAUACACUAUAAUUCCACUCAAUAAAAUUUCAGCCAGAUGUAUUGCACCAGAAACUCUGAGAGUUGCUCAGAAUCUUGUUGGCCCUGACAACGUUCAUGUGGCUCUUUCCUUGGUUGAAUAUAAACCAGAACUUCAGAAAGCAAUGGAGUUUGUCUUUGGAACAACAUUUGUUUGUGACAAUAUGGAUAAUGCCAAAAAAGUGGCCUUUGAUAAGAGGAUAAUGACUAGAACUGUAACUCUCGGAGGUGAUGUGUUUGAUCCUCAUGGGACAUUGAGUGGAGGUGCUCGAUCCCAGGCAGCUUCCAUUUUAACCAAGUUUCAAGAACUCAAAGAUGUUCAGGAUGAACUGAGAAUCAAAGAGAAUGAGCUGCGGGCUCUAGAAGAGGAAUUAGCAGGUCUUAAAAACACUGCUGAAAAGUAUCGCCAACUAAAACAGCAGUGGGAGAUGAAAACUGAAGAGGCAGAUUUAUUACAAACCAAGCUCCAGCAAAGCUCAUAUCACAAGCAACAAGAAGAAUUAGAUGCCCUUAAAAAAACCAUUGAGGAAAGUGAGGAGACUUUGAAAAACACUAAAGAAAUCCAAAGAAAAGCAGAAGAAAAAUAUGAAGUAUUGGAAAAUAAAAUGAAAAAUGCAGAAGCUGAAAGAGAGCGAGAACUGAAAGAUGCUCAGAAAAAACUGGAUUGUGCCAAAACAAAGGCAGAUGCAUCUAGCAAGAAGAUGAAAGAAAAACAACAGGAAGUUGAAGCUAUCACUCUGGAACUGGAAGAGCUCAAGAGAGAGCAUACAUCUUACAAACAACAGCUUGAAGCUGUAAAUGAAGCUAUCAAAUCCUAUGAAAGUCAGAUUGAAGUAAUGGCAGCUGAGGUGGCUAAAAAUAAGGAGUCAGUAAAUAAAGCUCAAGAAGAGGUGACCAAGCAAAAAGAGGUGAUAACAGCCCAAGACACUGUAAUUAAAGCUAAAUAUGCAGAAGUGGCAAAACACAAGGAGCAAAACAAUGAUUCUCAGCUUAAAAUUAAGGAAUUAGACCACAACAUCAGCAAACAUAAACGGGAGGCUGAAGAUGGUGCUGCAAAGGUAUCCAAAAUGUUGAAAGAUUAUGACUGGAUUAAUGCAGAGAGACACCUCUUUGGCCAACCCAAUAGUGCCUAUGAUUUCAAAACUAACAACCCUAAAGAAGCUGGUCAGAGACUUCAGAAGUUGCAAGAAAUGAAGGAGAAACUAGGAAGAAAUGUCAAUAUGAGAGCUAUGAAUGUAUUGACAGAAGCUGAAGAGCGAUACAAUGACUUGAUGAAGAAGAAGAGAAUUGUAGAAAAUGACAAAUCCAAAAUUCUUACAACUAUAGAAGACCUUGACCAGAAGAAAAACCAAGCCCUAAAUAUUGCAUGGCAAAAGGUGAACAAGGACUUUGGGUCUAUUUUUUCUACUCUUUUGCCUGGUGCUAAUGCUAUGCUUGCACCACCAGAGGGUCAAACUGUUUUGGAUGGUCUGGAGUUCAAGGUUGCCUUGGGAAAUACCUGGAAAGAAAACCUAACUGAACUUAGUGGUGGUCAGAGGUCUUUAGUGGCCUUGUCAUUAAUACUGUCCAUGCUUCUCUUCAAACCUGCUCCAAUUUAUAUCCUUGAUGAGGUAGAUGCAGCCUUGGAUCUUUCUCAUACCCAAAACAUUGGACAGAUGCUGCGUACUCAUUUCACACAUUCUCAGUUCAUUGUGGUGUCACUAAAAGAAGGUAUGUUCAACAAUGCAAACGUUCUUUUCAAAACCAAGUUUGUGGAUGGUGUUUCUACAGUAGCCAGAUUUACUCAAUGUCAAAAUGGAAAGAUUUCAAAGGAAGCAAAAUCCAAGGCAAAACCACCCAAAGGAGCACAUGUGGAAGUUUAAACUACAAAGUUAUUUCUUCAUCUUGACCUGUUUUUUUAAAUGUAAACUUUUAAGGACUUGAGAUAACUAAUUUGUUUAUAUACAAAAAUUAAUGUUACUGUGUUACUUAACCCAUGUUUUCUCUUUAUAUAAUCACUUAUCGCUUACAAAUGAGCAUAUAUUCCUCAUCUCUUAACUAGUCUAAUUAUGGUCCAAUUAUUGUGGUUGUGAUUUUAUGCAUAUCAUCAAAUGUUUUUUUCUUAUGCGGGUCUUUUAUAUAUUAGGGAUCCUGAGAUACCCGAUUCUAUAUGUAAAAGCUAAUAUACAAAAAAGCAGAUUAAAUUACAUGAUAAAUGUAGCUGAUCAUCAGUGUUUAAUUGAUUUAAUUCCUAAGGCAAUAUUAAUGUGUUUUCUAAAGUCAUUCAGGUAAGGAAGAAUUAUAAAUCAGGUAACUGGACCAACAAAGGGAACACAUAUAAAGCUAUUAUGCAUGCAUGGAGCCGUUUGAGGCUAGUUUUUUAAGGCCACAACUCCAGACCCCUGAUUUAGACUGAGAUAGGAAACAGAUCUUGAAAGAAUCCUUAUUUUAAUGAUACAUGAAUAUCAUGUUCCUAUACGCUUAAUAAUUGGUCUCUACGUUUUAAUGAUACAUGAAUAUCAUGUUCCUAUACGCUUAAUAAUUGGUCUCUACGACUUUAAUGUUUUUGUUUUUUUAAGCUGUGUAAGUAUUUUUAAAUCAAAGCUUAGGAGGUGUGUUGCGUGGUACUAUCUGCUGCAAAUUUAUCUGAAGUUUGUUAAUAUUUUCCAAGAUUUUUGUCAGCCUUUUCAUAAUCCAGUCAUUAACAACCUAUUGGUAAACAAGAAUGUAGGUGCCAGUAGACUAAACCAAAUUUAUUUUUCCCUGAGUCUGAUAUAUAUAUGUAUAAAUAUAAAUAACUCAAUCCAUCUGUUCCACCAAAAUAACUCAAAAGUUGGAUGAUUAUUUGUCUUCCGCUUUCCAGUUCAAAGGGAUGAAAUUCCUUUAGAACUUGAAAGAUGACACUAGCGAACACCAUGAGAAUACUGUCUACAGUUUUUGGUACGUCAUCACUAGAACAGUGACCCCAAACUGAAUCAUGAAAGGUCUGACAUGAUGUAAUCUGAUCUUCCAUGUGUUAUUUUGGCCCCACAUCUCUUCUUGAUUUUUUAGUCUUAUUUCCUUAGUGUUAUUAUCAUACUUCCCCUGAUAUAUGGCCGUACUUCCUGGCCCUGGGCUUGACAUUUCCCACCCUUCAUUCUCCAUACAUAUGAGAUGUCAGAAAACAUGCAGUAAUUGAUAUUAUGGGACACAUUGGAAAGGAUUGAAUCUGGAAUUAGUUCUGUCCACUGUGGAGGGGAGAGGAAAUAAUGCUGUAAAUGUUGAGUUACAGAAAGUCCAAUGUCAAAUAUAGUUUUUUUGUUUCCUUUCAAAUGUAUUACAGACUGUGCCAAAACAGUUACCAAUUCACACUGUCAAUAUUAAAGUAUACCAUAGUAUACAAAUUAGUCAGUACUUGCUGUUAAUUUUAAUAUUUCUGAUUUAACAGUUAGUUAUUAAGUGGUACUUCAUUGCUGUUUUAGCCAACGUUUUAAAAAUAAUUUGGGAGUUUGACUAUUUUGGCUUACGUACUCAUUUCCUUUUCUCUGCUAAAAAUGUUUUGCUUGUGUGCGUUCCUGAUUUUUGUCUUGUAUAAUCUUGAUCUUUGAAAACCCUCAAACAUGUAUUAAAUUGUUGUAACUUUUUUUCAUUAGAGGGAAGACAUUAAGGGGAUUGGGGACAUUUGUUUCACACAUCUGCAGUAAUAUGAGUUAACUAAUAUUUAACAAGCUCUUUCUUUACAUUAGCUGCUGUUCUCAUUUGUAUGUAUUGUCAUAUUUAAUCCUCAGAGUAACCUAGUGAGGUAAAUACUGUUGUUGUCAGCAUGGUGUAAUCGAGGAAUUGAGUGAGUUGAGCAGAAAAGUUAGGAAACUUGCUCAGGGUGAUAAUACAGUUAGGAGUGUCAGGGCCCAUGGACAAAUCUUGUCAGUCUCCAGAACCUAAGAUAUACUACGUCACUGACAGCUUGAACAUUUGUAUUUAUUGUACAGAAUAAAUUUAAGAAAAAUA